GAGACUCAGCCAGAGGAGUACGGAUUAAGUGGCCGAAGAAAGAGGAGUGAGGCAGGGGAGCGAGGCGGACGCUCCGAGCGCAUCGGACUCACCUGGGCCGGCGGCGACCGGCGAGUACGAGUGGACUCUUGCCCUCCGCAGCAUGCGCCCCGCCUGCUAAGUCGCCGCCGUCUCGCCCUCACCUAGCACCGCCAAUCCCGCCUGGAUGGAGUCCCCUCUGGGUUCCCAUUGGCUCCUGUGAGUGCUUGGGUGUCGGGAGCCUGUUUUUGGCGAGGGGAACCAACUUUUGAAGUUCGCCCAGAAGACUGCGUUCCAGCCCCAGUUCCCCGGCAGCGGGACCCGGCGAAGACGCGACCGCGGCGCGAGUCACCAUGGGAAGCAAAGGUGUCUACCAGUACCACUGGCAAAGCCACAAUGUCAAGCACAGUGGUGUGGACGACAUGGUGCUACUGUCCAAGAUCACAGAGAACUCCAUCGUGGAGAAUCUGAAGAAGAGAUACAUGGAUGACUACAUUUUUACAUAUAUAGGAUCUGUAUUAAUCUCAGUCAACCCUUUCAAGCAGAUGCCAUAUUUUGGGGAAAAGGAAAUUGAAAUGUACCAAGGAGCGGCACAGUAUGAAAACCCACCACAUAUCUAUGCCCUUGCAGAUAAUAUGUACAGAAACAUGAUCAUUGACAGAGAGAACCAGUGCGUCAUUAUCAGUGGUGAAAGUGGUGCUGGAAAAACAGUGGCUGCCAAAUAUAUCAUGAGCUACAUCUCCAGAGUGUCUGGAGGAGGGACCAAAGUCCAGCACGUGAAGGACAUUAUCCUGCAGUCCAACCCGCUGCUGGAGGCCUUCGGGAACGCCAAGACCGUCCGGAACAACAACUCCAGCCGAUUUGGAAAAUACUUUGAAAUCCAGUUCAGUCCAGGUGGGGAACCAGAUGGUGGAAAGAUCUCCAACUUCCUUCUGGAAAAAUCUAGGGUGGUGAUGAGGAACCCAGGAGAGCGGAGUUUUCACAUAUUUUACCAGCUCAUCGAGGGCGCCUCUGCAGAGCAGAAACACAGCCUUGGCAUCACCAGCAUGGACUAUUAUUACUACCUGAGCCUCUCGGGCUCAUACAAGGUUGAUGACAUUGACGACAGGCGGGAGUUUCAGGAAACUCUGCACGCCAUGAAUGUGAUUGGGAUCUUUGCAGAAGAGCAAACGCUGGUGUUGCAGAUAGUGGCGGGUAUUCUCCACCUGGGAAACAUCAGCUUCAAAGAAGUUGGCAACUACGCGGCUGUGGAGAGUGAAGAGUUUUUAGCUUUUCCUGCAUAUCUGCUAGGGAUAAACCAGGACCGGUUGAAAGAAAAGCUAACAAGCCGGCAGAUGGAUAGCAAGUGGGGAGGCAAAUCCGAAUCCAUCCACGUGACCCUCAACGUAGAGCAGGCCUGUUACACCCGGGAUGCGCUCGCCAAGGCCCUGCACGCCCGGGUCUUUGAUUUCUUGGUAGAUUCCAUCAAUAAAGCCAUGGAGAAAGACCAUGAAGAAUACAACAUUGGCGUCCUAGACAUCUAUGGCUUUGAAAUAUUCCAGAAAAAUGGCUUUGAACAGUUUUGUAUCAAUUUUGUUAAUGAAAAACUGCAGCAGAUUUUUAUUGAACUGACAUUAAAGGCAGAACAGGAAGAAUAUGUUCAAGAGGGAAUAAGAUGGACACCCAUUGAGUACUUUAAUAAUAAAAUCGUAUGUGACCUCAUAGAGAACAAAGUGAACCCUCCUGGCAUCAUGAGCAUCCUGGAUGACGUGUGCGCCACGAUGCAUGCGGUGGGUGAGGGGGCAGAUCAGACGCUGCUCCAGAAACUUCAGAUGCAGAUUGGGAGUCAUGAGCACUUCAACAGUUGGAACCAAGGCUUCAUCAUUCAUCAUUAUGCUGGGAAGGUAUCCUAUGACAUGGAUGGCUUUUGUGAAAGGAACCGGGAUGUGCUUUUUAUGGAUCUCAUCGAGCUUAUGCAGAGCAGCGAGCUGCCUUUCAUAAAGUCUUUAUUUCCGGAAAAUCUGCAGGCUGACAAGAAAGGGCGCCCAACUACUGCCGGAAGCAAAAUAAAGAAACAAGCCAAUGACCUUGUGAGCACCCUGAUGAAAUGUACGCCCCACUACAUUCGCUGCAUCAAGCCAAACGAAACCAAGAAGCCCAGAGACUGGGAGGAAAGCAGGGUAAAGCAUCAAGUCGAAUAUUUGGGUCUGAAAGAGAACAUUCGAGUGAGAAGAGCUGGCUAUGCCUAUCGGCGCAUCUUCCAAAAAUUCCUACAGAGGUAUGCCAUUCUGACCAAAGCCACCUGGCCUUCUUGGCAGGGAGAGGAGAAGCAAGGCGUCCUGCACCUGCUGCAGUCGGUCAACAUGGACAGCGACCAGUUCCAGCUGGGGAGGAGUAAAGUGUUCAUCAAAGCCCCCGAGUCUCUAUUUCUUUUAGAAGAGAUGAGAGAGAGAAAGUAUGAUGGGUAUGCUCGAGUGAUACAGAAAUCAUGGAGGAAAUUCGUGGCCCGGAAGAAAUACGUUCAAAUGAGAGAAGAAGCCUCAGACCUCUUAUUGAACAAGAAGGAGAGAAGGAGAAACAGUAUUAACAGGAACUUUAUAGGGGAUUAUAUUGGGAUGGAAGAGCACCCAGAACUCCAGCAGUUCGUGGGCAAGAGGGAGAAGAUUGAUUUCGCAGACACAGUCACCAAGUAUGACAGGAGGUUCAAGGGUGUAAAGCGAGACCUGCUCCUUACCCCAAAGUGCUUGUACUUAAUCGGACGAGAAAAAGUCAAACAGGGCCCAGACAAGGGCCUGGUGAAAGAAGUCCUGAAGCGGAAAAUCGAGAUAGAACGGAUCUUGUCUGUGUCCCUCAGUACUAUGCAGGAUGACAUUUUUAUUCUCCAUGAGCAAGAGUAUGACAGUUUGCUUGAAUCUGUCUUCAAAACUGAAUUCCUAAGCCUCUUAGCAAAGCGUUACGAGGAGAAGACCCAGAAGCAACUACCUCUGAAAUUCAGCAAUACGCUUGAACUGAAGUUGAAAAAGGAAAACUGGGGCCCCUGGAGUGCAGGGGGCUCCCGGCAAGUGCAGUUCCACCAAGGGUUUGGGGACCUGGCUGUCCUCAAGCCCAGUAACAAAGUGCUGCAGGUCAGCAUCGGACCUGGACUGCCCAAGAACUCCCGUCCUACCAGAAGGAACACUACCCAAAAUACAGGUUAUUCCAGUGGGACUCAAAAUGCCAACUACCCAGUGAGAGCUGCCCCUCCUCCCCCAGGAUACCAUCAGAACGGAGUCAUCAGAAACCAGUAUGUGCCAUAUCCCCAUGCUCCUGGAAGCCAGAGGUCCAAUCAGAAAAGCCUGUACACCUCCAUGGCCCGCCCGCCCUUGCCUCGGCAGCAGUCUACCAGUUCAGACCGAGUGUCACAGACGCCAGAGAGCCUGGAUUUCCUCAAGGUCCCGGACCAGGGAGCUGCAGGGGUCAGGAGACAAACAACCAGUCGGCCUCCCCCAGCAGGGGGCAGACCCAAGCCCCAGCCCAAGCCCAAGCCUCAGGUGCCACAGUGCAAGGCUUUGUAUGCCUAUGACGCUCAGGACACAGACGAACUCAGCUUUAAUGCCAAUGACAUUAUUGAUAUUAUCAAAGAAGAUCCUUCUGGCUGGUGGACGGGUCGACUACGAGGCAAGCAGGGCCUGUUCCCCAACAACUAUGUGACCAAGAUCUGAGGUGCCCGUGACUCUGACACAUGGGGCAGAGGAGCUCCAGGCACAGACCAGGGGAGGGGAUAUUUAGGGGCUCCCCUUACAAUCCACAAUGAGCAAUUGCUUCUCCAAGGCCUGGAGCUAUUCUGGUACCUUCCCCAUGGAGGACACUGAAAAGGCUGGGUUGGGGACAGGGAGUAUCACUCCAUAAGUGAUCCUAAAAGGUAGCCUCUUCAUAGGAACCCAGGAGGACAAAACCACCAUGCAUUAAGAUUUAUUUAUUGUAUUUAAACCUGGUGAGAGGACAAGUGAGGUCUGCUCAGACCUUGUAGGCUUCUAUCAAAACAGCACCCUGCUUGCUCACCAGGCCUAGAGAAUGGCUGUAGGUGGCCGCUGACAAGUGCCUUUAGUUGAAGAGCACAUUUCUUUCAUCUCUCUUGUCCAUACCUGAUAGACACAUUCCUCUCUGCCACCUUCCUUCAGGGAGGACCCGCCCUCUGCAGACUGGGCUUAGCGUGAGCAGGCACUUCCCAUGUACGUGCCAAGGGUAAGCUGGCCUGCUGAGCCCAGGGCGACAGAGGGGCACUGGUUUACACUUUGCCGGGACCAUCAGGGCCGCCAAGCAGGUCAGGGGCUGGGGGCUGGGGGCUGGGCUGCUGGCUUUGCUUUCUCUGGGUCUUCAAUUAGAAUGUGGCUGGCCCAUAUUGGUUUGUGUUUAAAUGCUGUACUUACUACAAGAAGGAUCUUUUUUCAAGCUGUACAUUUAUAAAAACAGAUCAUAUACUGUAUAUAUAAAAAUCUUGAGAUGGUAGAAACAUGUAUGAAUGUACUAAGUAGUAUUCCACUGUACUCAUUCAUAAGGUAGGUUUUCUUACAAAACUCACACCAGGUACUUAAAGAUGUGCUCUGCUUUUUUCCAACUACGGAGUGUCACUGCUUUCUAGGUCAGUCCCUGCAGACUCUUCUCAACUCUUUCCCUAUAGGAAACUUACUCCGCGUCCUGCCCCCACCUCCUAAAUAAAUAAAGGAAUCGGCGAACACCUUCUUCUUUUAUGACAUUUGUUAUGGGUUGAAUUGUGUGCCUCCAAAGAAGAUGUUGGAGUCCCAGCCACCAGUACCUCACAAUAUGACCUUAUUUGGAAAUAGAGUCUUUAUGGAGCAAACAAACAAAACUAAUUAAAAUGAAGUCAUUAGAGUGGGUCUUAAUCCAAUAUAAUGGUGUCCUGAUGAAAAGGGGAAAUUUGGACACAGAGACCAACAUGCCAGAGGAAAGACCAUGUGAAAAGGCAGGGAGAAGACAGCCAUUCACAAGCCCUGGACAGAGGCCUGGAACAGAUUCUCCCUCACACCCUCACAAGGAACCAGCCCUGCCCACCUUGGUCUUGGACUUCCAACCUCCAGAACUGUGAGGCAAUACAUUUCGCUGUUUAAGCCACUCGGUUUGUGGUAGUUUGUUACGGCAGCCCUAACAAACUAAAACAAUGUUUUCUUGCCAUAAUAGUGAAAAGCUGGAAUCAGUGUAAUGCCCAUCAAUAAUGGAAUGGUUGUAAGUAGAGACUGCCAUUUCUCUACCUUUCCUCCUCUGGGUGCCAUAGCCAUUCUUAAGCUACUGGUAACUUAGAGUUUGAGCAGCAUACACCUUUGAGGCUUUCAGGAUCCUCAAGUCCAUGGGAAAAAAUUAUCAGGGCUUACGUAUAAGGGAAAAAAAUUGAUCUAGAUUUGAAACGAAGAUACAUUUAAUUCUGCUGUGUUUUACUUCAAGAACAGGGAGCAAACUCCAUUCUGUAACAGUAACGAAUAAUGUUAAAAGGCUACUUCAGUUCCAUGUUGCGACCAGAGAGGAAAGUAGAGCCAUGAUGCGGUGAGUUGAGGAAAGGUAAUCCUGUUGACACUAGUGGUCUCUAAAGUACUUUCACAUUCAUGGACUCCCCGCAGUGGGAGGAAGAUACCACCAGAACUGGGACAGAGGAGCAUGCUGGAGUCCCCACAGCCACCAGCACUCAGGCUGCGUUCUCAGGGCAGGAACACCAGGACCAUCUUCCCUUGUUAUCAUAAGCCCCUGGCUGGCUGGGACAAGCCUUUGUUUUUCCUCCUGAUUGAUUGAUUGGCAUUUUACACUUGUGUGUAACUGGGAACCAUCGGGCUCUAGGUCACAAAACAGGGACUGAGUUAAACCCCCACGAGUAACACCCUCAUCCAUGGAAAUCACAGACCAAGCCCUUAGCACCUGCAUCGUGUGCCCAGCCAGUGCCAGGCUCAAGGAGAUGCCCAACAAAUGGUGCUGAAAUAGGUAAGUGACCCACAGGGGAAGGAGACUUAGAUCUGCGUAGAGAUGCUGAAAUGCUGACACUAUUAAGAAAAGUUUGGAGAAAUAGUGGUUUAUCUUAAACUUAUUUGUAUAUAUUUAGAAAUUCAACAUGGGGACUACCAGAAAAAUCUGGGAUAAAUAACAUUUCCCUUUUUUUCCUAAUUAAAAAGUCUUCAGAAAAAUGUCUUUUUUCCCUUUAAGACACUAACCUGGGUUUCCUCUAGUCUGUGGAUCUAGCCUGGCCUGCCAUUUUGUUCACUGUGCAGUUAAGCAAAUAUGACCACUUUAGGAGUCACUUACCAGGAAAGAACAUACAGAAGAUCAAGGGGCCACCCCCACCUUCUGGAACUUGCCAUCCUGUUUGAAAUAAGGGGUGUUCAUGUGCACACACAGCAACGUGUAUAGCAGUAUCAAACACAGUAUAAAAAUGUGACAUCCCUUCAACCAAAGGUUUUAAGUAACCAGGAACUAAAUGAGAAGGCCUGACUGUGUACCCUAGGGUAGAGGUGUUCAAGCUUUAGUUGUAGAAGAGAGAGAGACAGAGGUCUGUAUAAGGGUGGUAUCCACUCUACUGAUGGCCGUCUGUGAGACAGAGAGAGGCUGAUCUGAAACUCCUGGGAUCAAACGAUCCUCCUGCCUCAGCCUCUCAAAGUGCUGGGAUUAUGGGCAAGAGCCACCGUACCUGGCCAACUGGCUUAAAGACAUGCAAAAGGGCCGUCUCUUCCACAGUGUUUUGUGAAACAAUACAGAGACAUGUGGAGAGGACAAAGGGUGAAGCCUUCUUGAAUAAGCUUGCUCCCCAACCAUGAAGGAUGCCAACCCACUGACCUCCCAACGUGUGGUCCCAGCCCAUCGUAAUCAAACCUGACUCCCCACUACUACCAAGUCCAGCCCAAUGAAGGUAGAAAAGCAUCGUGCAGUUUCCUCCUUAAAGGACCUGCCCUGUGUGCACACCAUGUCCACCAAUAUUCUGCUGGCCAGAGCUUAGUCAUGUGGCCUCAACUCAAGGGGGCUGGAGGUCUCUGCACAGAGCUGUCUCAGCAGCUUACCCAGAGCACCAGAGUGACAGCGGGCUCCUGCCAGGUGGAAGUGUUCACAAAAAUGAGUAAGAGAAAAUAUGGAUGUGCCUUUAUGAAUUACAAACUCCAUGGGCUUCCAUAGAGCAUGGCUUUUACAUAAUCUAAAUUCCUUCUCUUUGCGACUCCCUCCUGAACUCAUCCCCAGACCCUCCCUGAGUGGAGCUGGUCACACCAAGUCAGCCUGUGCCUCUAGUUGCUACCAUUUCUUUUAUAGGUGUUGUCCCAGUUAAGAUUUCACUGGCAGUAGGGCUGGAUUCUGGUUUCCAGGGCAAUCAAGAGCAGAGCAUGAACGGUGCGUCUUUGGUAGACAAUUUAACUCUGUGUUUCUGGCACCCCUCACUUUUGUGAUCAAAAGAAAGACCAGAGGAGCCUUUCUGCAAUUCUGCCCUCUUUCCCUGUUUUGCUUUUCUCCCAAGGCCUAGCUGAUUGAUUGCAGUUCUUUCUGGAUUUAGUAACUUGGUUUUAUUCCUACCCACUAAUCUUGAUGUCUUUUUCCCUACUAGAUCAUACCUUUCCACUCUGAGCACCCUUUCUAACAAGAAGACUGGCUCAGUAUGGUUCACUAGGUCGCCCAAGGUCACACAGUUCUUCCCUGGGGGAGCCAUCACAGGAACUCUGAGUCAAAGGCCUGUGCGUUUUUAUUUUCAGACAGCACCUCACUUUGUCACCCAGACUAGAGAACAGUGGUGCGAUCAUGCCUUACUGCAGUCUCAAACUCCAGGGCUCAGGUGAUCCUCCCACCUCAGCCUCCCAAGUAGCUGGGACCACAAGCAUGUGCCACCACAUUCGGCUAAUUAUUUGUACAGAUGGGGUCUCCCUGUGUUGCCCAGCUGGUCUCAAAGCUCUGGGCUCAAGCAGUCUUCCCGCCUUGGCCUCCCAAAAUUCUGGGAUUACAAGCAUGAGCCACUGUGCCCAAAAGGCCUGUGCUUUUAAUCAUUUUCUCCAAUUCAACAGAUAUUUAGUAAUGUGAUGGUCUACUGUGUCAGCCUUUCAACUUCCAAUAUCUUCCUCUCAGAACAUAAAAGUCUAUUUAAAAAGAGAGAGAGAAGAAAACUCACGCAUAAAACUCAACAGCUAGAAACUUGUAAGCUCCUUUAAUGGGCAGGAGCUCCAUCUAACAAAUCUGAAUCCUCUGAUUCAUCUCUUUCCAAGACCAUUAACCUUCUCUUUAAAAUAAUUAACAGCUAUGUUCAAGUAUCUUCUUCACACUAGAAGCUAUACUAAGUGCUUGGCAUACUUUACUUAGCACCACCCUAUGAGGGAGACACUCUUAUCCCCACUUCACAGGUACAGAAACUAAAGUAUAGAGAUCACCACUACUUAAAAUCAAACCCAAAGCACCCACGUUCAGAGUUAGUGCUCUUCUAUACUAUGGAUACAUCAUCUCAUUUUUAAUUUCCGUGUUUUUAUGAUAUGGUUUCUACUUCUGCCACUCAUUUCCCAUUUAUGACAUUUUAGUUUGGGGUGCCUGCUGUGCCAUCUAAGAAAGUAUCUUAAAGGUCUUUUUUUAUGACAUCCUGGAAGAAUUUCCUAAGUCAGGACAUUUAAUAUUUAACUAAGUAAAAUAUGUAAUAAGGAAGCUA